ACAGAGAGAUUCACGCACCCUCAAGAGUGUGGGUGAGACAUAUACAGCCUGUUAGACCUGAAGGCAGAUGGCUCUUCUUAAGGCCAAUAAGGAUCUCAUUUCCGCAGGAUUGAAGGAGUUCAGCGUUCUGCUGAAUCAGCAGGUCUUCAAUGAUCCUCUCGUCUCUGAAGAAGACAUGGUGACUGUGGUGGAGGACUGGAUGAACUUCUACAUCAACUAUUACAGGCAGCAGGUGACAGGGGAGCCCCAAGAGCGAGACAAGGCUCUGCAGGAGCUUCGGCAAGAGCUGAACACUCUGGCCAACCCUUUCCUGGCCAAGUACAGGGACUUCCUGAAGUCUCAUGAGCUCCCGAGUCACCCACCGCCCUCCUCCUAGCUCAGGGACCCAGCCCCUCCUCUCUGAGAAACUCUGACCUUCAUGUCCUUAGGCUGUGCUCCUGCCACUCUACCCUGACACCUCAAUAAAGACCAGUGCUGGUUUUGUUGGA